AAUUUCUACGCGCACCGGAAGACGGAGGUCCUCUUUCCUUGCCUAACGCAGCCAUGGCUCGUGGUCCCAAGAAGCAUCUGAAGCGGGUGGCAGCUCCAAAGCAUUGGAUGCUGGAUAAAUUGACCGGUGUGUUUGCUCCUCGUCCAUCCACCGGUCCCCACAAGUUGAGAGAGUGUCUCCCCCUCAUCAUUUUCCUGAGGAACAGACUUAAGUAUGCCCUGACAGGAGAUGAAGUAAAGAAGAUUUGCAUGCAGCGGUUCAUUAAAAUCGAUGGCAAGGUCCGAACUGAUAUAACCUACCCUGCUGGAUUCAUGGAUGUCAUCAGCAUUGACAAGACGGGAGAGAAUUUCCGUCUGAUCUAUGACACCAAGGGUCGCUUUGCUGUACAUCGUAUUACACCUGAGGAGGCCAAGUACAAGUUGUGCAAAGUGAGAAAGAUCUUUGUGGGCACAAAAGGAAUCCCUCAUCUGGUGACUCAUGAUGCCCGCACCAUCCGCUACCCCGAUCCCCUCAUCAAGGUGAAUGAUACCAUUCAGAUUGAUUUGGAGACUGGCAAGAUUACUGAUUUCAUCAAGUUCGACACUGGUAACCUGUGUAUGGUGACUGGAGGUGCUAACCUAGGAAGAAUUGGUGUGAUCACCAACAGAGAGAGGCACCCUGGAUCUUUUGACGUGGUUCACGUGAAAGAUGCCAAUGGCAACAGCUUUGCCACUCGACUUUCCAACAUUUUUGUUAUUGGCAAGGGCAACAAACCAUGGAUUUCUCUUCCCCGAGGAAAGGGUAUCCGCCUCACCAUUGCUGAAGAGAGAGACAAAAGACUGGCGGCCAAACAGAGCAGUGGGUGAAAUGGGUCCCUGGGUGACAUGUCAGAUCUUUGUACGUAAUUAAAAAUAUUGUGGCAGGAUUAAUAGCAUUUUGGUUUUGUGGGUUGUUUUUUUUUUUAAUUCAGUUUCCUGCUAUUUUACUGUAUAACAUGAACAGUGAUUAAGUUCUCAGGCAGGCUUAGGCAGUCUGUUAUUGGCUGGGCUUAGUUAGUGGUGGGAAGUAGAAGAUACCAGACUUGGGAAAGGAACAGCAACUAACCAAGGAGUAGAAAGAGCCAAGAAAUCCCGGAGUAUUUAUCUCCCCCGCCUUGACUUGGCCAAGAACUUCUCUACACAGUGGACCCCUCUGCCCUGUUAAGUUCCCUUGGCUUUCUAAAAAUCUGCCCUCAUUUUCUUCUCCAGUCUGUAUUGCACUAGCCCAUCCACAAGCCUGGCUCAUCUGUUUUUCCCACUCCUGUGCCCAUCUUGCCAAACGCAGGAUGAAAAUCUCCAGUUGCCAUUAAAGGUGGUCAUAAAUGGGCUGUUGAUGUUGCAAAGCAUUGCAGUUCCUUGGACUUAGUGCCCUUAUUCUCCAGCUGCCGCUGCAGUCCUCAACUCUGUUUUUCAGAGGACAGAGAUGUAGAACAUAAACUUGUUCUUGCUUGUCCAAA